GGGCUGUCUCGGAAACUCAGAGCCGGGUUCCUCCCGGGUUUCUGCCGGGUUUCUCCCUGCGGCUCCUGGGUUGUUGAGACUCUUGUGAAGAUGGCUUGCGCUGCCGCGCGGUCCCCGGCCGACCAGGACAGGUUUAUUUGUAUCUAUCCUGCUUAUUUAAAUAAUAAGAAGACCAUCGCAGAGGGAAGGCGAAUCCCCAUAAGUAAGGCUGUUGAAAAUCCUACAGCUACAGAGAUUCAAGAUGUAUGUUCAGCAGUUGGACUUAACGUAUUUCUUGAGAAAAAUAAAAUGUACUCUAGAGAAUGGAAUCGUGAUGUCCAAUACAGAGGCAGAGUCCGGGUCCAGCUCAAACAGGAAGAUGGGAGCCUCUGCCUUGUACAGUUCCCAUCACGUUAAGAAUGUCUGAGGGGUCAGGCGGUGCUGGCAAGAUGGCUGCACUUGAGAAGAUGACGUUUCCCAAGAAGAUGACAUUUCCAGAGAAACCAAGCCACAAAAAGUACAGGGCCGCCCUGAAGAAGGAGAAACGAAAGAAACGUCGGCAGGAACUUGCUCGACUGAGAGACUCAGGACUCUCACAGGAGGAGGAAGAGGACACUUUUAUUGAAGAACAACAACUAGAAGAAGAGAAGCUAUUGGAAAGAGAGAGGGAAAGAUUACAUGAGGAGUGGUUGCUGAGGGAGCAGAAGGCACAAGAAGAAUUCAGAAUAAAGAAGGAAAAGGAAGAGGCGGCUAAAAAAUGGCUAGAAGAACAAGAGAGAAAGUUAAAGGAACAAUGGAAAGAACAGCAGAGGAAAGAGAGAGAAGAGGAGGAGCAGAAACAACAGGAGAAGAAAGAAAAAGAGGAAGCUGUGCAGAAGAUGCUGGAUCAGGCUGAAAAUGAUUUAGAAAAUAGUACCACAUGGCAAAACCCAGAACCACCCGUGGAUUUCAGAGUAAUGGAGAAGGAUCGAGCUAAUUGUCCCUUCUACAGUAAAACAGGAGCUUGCAGAUUUGGAGACAGAUGUUCACGUAAACAUAAUUUCCCAACAUCUAGUCCUACCCUUCUUAUUAAGAGCAUGUUUACAACGUUUGGAAUGGAGCAGUGCAGGAGGGAUGACUAUGACCCUGACGCAAGCCUGGAGUACAGCGAGGAAGAAACCUACCAACAGUUCCUAGAUUUCUAUGAGGAUGUGUUGCCCGAGUUCAAGAACGUGGGGAAAGUGAUUCAGUUCAAGGUCAGCUGCAAUUUGGAACCUCACCUGAGGGGCAAUGUAUAUGUUCAGUACCAGUCGGAAGAAGAAUGCCAAGCAGCCCUUUCUCUGUUUAACGGACGAUGGUAUGCAGGACGACAGCUGCAAUGUGAAUUCUGCCCAGUGACCCGGUGGAAAAUGGCGAUUUGUGGUUUAUUUGAAAUACAACAAUGUCCAAGAGGAAAACACUGCAACUUUCUUCAUGUGUUCAGAAAUCCCAACAAUGAAUUCUGGGAAGCUAAUAGAGACAUCUACUUGUCUUCAGAUCAGACUGGCUCCUCCUUUGGCAAGAACUCCGAGAGGAGGGAGAAGAUGGGCCACCACGACCACUACUACAGCAGGCAGCGGGGAAGGAGAAACCCUAGUCCAGACCACACCUACAAAAGAAAUGGGGAAUCCGAGAGAAAAAAGAGUAGUCAUAGGGGGAAGAAAUCUCACAAACGCACAUCAAAGAGUCGGGAGAGGCACAAUUCACCAAGCAGAGGAAGAAAUAGGCACCGCAGCUGGGACCAGGGCCGCCGGAGCCAGAGCCGCAGGAGCCACCGCAGCCGGAGCCAAAGUUCCUCUAGGUGCCGAAGUCGUGGGAGGAGGAAGUCGGGUAAUAGAGACAGAACUGUUCAGAGUCCCCAAUCCAAAUAAACUAGUUUUGUUCUUAAAAAAAAAAAAAAAAAAAAAAAGAAUGGACCAGGCCAGGUAUAGUGGCUCACACCUGUAAUCCCAGCACUUUAGGAGGCUGAGGUGGGUGGAUCACUUGAGGUCAGGAGUUUGAGGCCAGCCUGGCCAACAUGGCAAAACCCCAUUUCUACUAAAAAUACAAAAAUUAGCCAGGUGUGGUGGCAGGCGUCUGUAAUCCAAGCUACUUGGGAAGCUGAGGCAGGAGAAUCGCUUGAAUCUGGAAGGCGGAGGUUGCAGUGAGUCGACAUCAUGCCACUUCACUCCAGCCUGGGUGACAGAGCGAGACUGUGUCUCAAAAAAUAGAAUUUUUGGACUAGUGGAACUACACAGCCUGCUUUCCAUAUCAGACCAUUCAAUCCAAUGGGAUUCACUGCCAUAAUCUCCAUGUUAUGAUUUUAAGCCAGGCCUCUCUUCACCUUUCCUAUUCCUUACAUUUAAAGACUCCAAAGCUUGUUUACUGAGCACAGAUCUUGGAAAACAGGAUCUUCAGACUUGGGAAAGCAUGACAGUAGAUGAUGGAAAGGUAAAGACUCAGACUAGCAUCUAGUAGUCUCGCUACACAUGGAUAGUAAUGCUACGUGCAUGAAUGUGCAAUCAUGCAAAAACUCAAAUCAGCCUUCUGCACACACACAAUGGUAGACUAAGACCUUCUGUUAAAGGUCCAAGCACUCCAAGGAAGCCAGCGCCUUGAGGUACCCUCAGUAUGUGCAAGUAGUUCGAUGUUACUCUUAGUUUUCCCAGCAACUCUGCUCUAGCAUGCCCUAAGUUUAGCCAGCAGCAGAUCUUACUGAAUUAUAAGAUGUUGCCAGAGGUUCAGAACCUUGGUUUUUUUGAGAUACGCAUUUGCAUUGACCCAAAAUGGAGAAUUAAAUGACUGUAUUUUUCACUGGCAUUAGCUUUGUUUCCUUGGCAUAGUGCCAGUUAAUUACAGCAGACCCUGCAAGACCACCUCUCUAGUUAUUUCCCUGUGGAAGCCUUUUGGUUGGUUUUGUUUUUUUGGUUUUUUUUGUUUUUUUUUUUUUUUUGAGACGGAGUCUUGCUCUGUUGCCAGGCGGGAGUGCAGUGGCGUGAUCAGCUCACUGCAACCUCCGCCUCCCAGAUUCAAGUGAUUCCCCUGCCUCAACCUCUCGAGUAGCUGGUACUACAGGCGCAUGCCACCGUGCCCAGCUAAUUUUUUGUAUUUUAGUAGAGACAGGGUUUCACCAUGUUGGCCAGGAUGGUCUUGAUCUGACCUCGUGAUCUGCCCACCUUGGCCUCCUAAUGUGCUUAGGAUUAUAGGCGUGAGCCACUGCACCCUGCUGCCUUUUGGUUUUUAAUAUCCAAAAUUCAUACAAUGUUUUACUGUAGUUGCUUAUAUAGGAAAAGCUAUACAUCCCCAAAAUGCAAUACAACAUUAUGAUAUGCAGGAAAUGUCUUGAGUAACAUUUUUGACAGAAUAUCAGAAUCCUUGGUGGACAUUUUGAAGAAUAUGCAGAGCAUCACAGGGGAUGUGCUAUGUAUUCCUGCACACAGAGCAAUUGUUACUUACUAUAUUAACUAUUUGGAGAGCAGCAAGUGUUUUUAGCAUCUAACAUCCUAACAUGAUAUUUGUUAUAUAUAGGUAUUUUGCUGUAUUUUAUUAAUACUUAGUGAAUUCGUUGAGUUUUACAUUGACAUGUAAUACAUUAAAAUUUUUCCCACUUAAAAUAGUGGAAAAUAAGCUUCUGCAUAGAAUGUAUUCCUACAUAGAAUAUCUGAUUUUCAGAAAUGGAUUAUCAAGAGAGAGACAGAUGUCCAUAUUAAAACCAGAGCAUUAAGGUGAAGUGAAAAUGACUCAUUGGAUUAAGAAUCAGGAGAGGUGGGGCUGGGCGCAGUGGCUUACGCCUGUAAUCCCAGCACUUUAGGAGGCCGAGGCAGGUGGAUCACGAGGUCAGGAGUUCGAGACCAUCCUGGCCAACAUGGUGAAACCCUGUCUCUACUAAAAUUAGAAAAAAAAUAGCCGGGCAUUGUGGUGGGCACCCGUAGUCCCAGCCACUCAGGAGGCUGAGGCAGGAGAAUCACUGGAACCCAGGAGGCGGAGGUUACAGUGAGCUGAGAUUGCGCCACUGCACUCCAGCCUGGCGACAGAGCGAGACUCUGUCUCAAAAAAAAAAAAAAAAAAAAAUCAGGAGAGGUGGGGUGUGUUUUAUGACUUUAGGCAAAUCAACCUAAGAGACAGUUUUCUCUUCUGCAGAGUUUUAGGAAAGUCACAAAUUAAUGUACUUGAAGAAAGUGUACAAUAGAAUAGUAGUAUUACCAAAUCCUAAAGUUCUUAUUGUGGAAAAUCUCUGAAAUAUUACCUGCCUAUGUAGAUGCCAACCCUUCAGCAAUCCAGACAAGCUUAUUAUCUUUUCUGGAUGAAUUAAGUGUCCACAGUUUUGUACCUCUUCAAUGUGAUUACUUUGUAGGCUAGACUGCAGACUGUUAAUUGACUACUUUCUGGUACCCUCUAGCUAUUGUCUUGAGACAGUAAAAUAAUUACUGCUCUCUAGCUACAUCCUUAGCAUUUUCCUGUUCUGAAAUGAAAUCAUUUUCUUAUGUUAAAAAUAAAGUUAAUUACUGUUCAACUCCCAAGGUGAUAUUCAGCUGCCACCUCUUACAACCCUCUCUUCUUAAUCUGUGUAACUAUUCUACAGCCCAGGAAUAGCCUGAGUUUAUUAAAGUCACCCACACAGAUCUGGCUCUUUUCAAUCAAGCUGCCCUCAAAGUGCCAGCUGAUGAUACUCCCAAGGAGACUCACAAGCCCACUGCUGCCUGCAGUUCAGACAGAGUCCAUGCUAUUUUAACUGGACUCUUGGCACUAUUAGCACUGACACAAUGACUCCUUAAAUUACGAAUUACAACAGGCCAUUCUAUUCCGUCUGUGCUUCUAAUGCUGUCACCAUGUGAUUUUCCCCCAGAAGAGAUAUUUCCCAGGUAGGGGUAUGCUUAACAUGCAGUUACGGAACUGAGAGUUAAUGUCAGAAGAAAGCUUUUGCAGUGUAGCCACAGAAUAGUUACAGGCUACAUUGCUCAGCAUGCACAAAUAAAAGCUUAAAAGAACGUGUUAAAGGAAAGAUUUCCCUGUCUUUUUAGCCUCCUACGAACAUUAAGAAGAAAAAUGUUGCGAGGCACAGUGGCUUACGCCUGUAAUCCUAGCACUCUGGGAGGCUGAGGUGUCCAAGAGGAUCACCUGAGGUCAGGAGUUUGAGACCAGCCUGGCCAACAUGGUGAAACCCCAUCUCUACUAAAAAUACAAAAUUUGCCUAGCGUGGUGGUGGGCACCUGUAAUCCCAGCUACUUGGGAGGCUGAGGCAGGAGAAUUGCUUGAAUGCGGGAAGUACAGGUUGCAGUGAGCAGAGAUCACGCCACUUCACUCCACUCCAGCCUGAGUGAAAUAGCGAAACUCCAUCUCAAAAAAAAGAAAAAAGAAAAGAAAAAUGUUAUAUUCUCUGUCAAUGGGUGAAAUAGCACAGGUGACAAUUCAGGUCAGGACCUAAUCUUGCCAGAGUUUACUCAACCUUGUUCUAAAAAUAAAUCUAGCCAGGCCUGGUGGCUCACGCCUGUAAUUGCAGCACUUCGGGAGGCUGAGGUGGGUGGAUCACAAGGUCAGGAGUUGAGACCAGCCUGGCCAACAUGGUGAAACCCCGUCUCUACUAAAAAUACAAAAAUUAGCCGGGCGUGGUUGUGCACCUGUAGUCCCAGCUACUCGGGAGGCUGAGACAGGAGAAUCACUUGAACCUGGGAAAGAGGUUACAGUGAGCAGAGGUCACGCCACUGCACUCCAGCCUGGGCGACAGAGCAAGACUCCGUCUCAAAAAAAGUAAAGUAAAUCUAGAAAAUGAUUUAAAUGAAGGUAAACAGAGGAUACAAAGAUAUUAAUUGCAGCAUUAUGUAUAAUCGCAUGACAAAUGUCCUCAAUGUCUUUCAAUUGGGAAGUAGGUAAAUUAUCAAUAACAUUAGAUAGCUAUGUCAAAAAAUACUGAAUAACAUGAGAAAAUACUCAGAAUACUGUGUUAAUUGAAAAAAGCAAGACACAGAAUUAUAUAUCAUAUGUGAUCUAAGCCACACAUAUGUUAAGACAGCAAUACAUACAUAUAUAUAUACACAUACACACAGAGUUCUGUUUUUAUUUAUAUACACAGACCAAUAUAUUUGCACAUUUUAAAAAAUAGGAAGACUACUCUAAGAUGUAGGAUUACAAAUGUUAUUUUCCUCCCUACAUAAAACACAUCCCAUCACACACACACACACACACACACACACACACACACACACACACAAAUGUAAACAGUAGGACAACAAGGACUUUGUUUUAUUCGCCAAAGUAUCUCCCAGAUGUAGAACAGAAUCUGGCACAUGGAGGUUCUAAAUAAAUCUGCUGAAUAAAGGAAUGAGCAUAUGUAAAUUUCAUAAUCAAGAAAAAAAGCUUUUAAAUUUAUUUUUAAACCCUCUUGCUCAAGGCCAGAUGUCAGAGCAAAGCUCAGAAUAUGCAUGAUCCAAUUUCUACCUAAAUACAUCAUAUAUUAUCUUCUCAACUAAGCUUUGAUGCCAAGCCAUUGGCUCCUUUUAUUUUCCUCCAAUCUUAUCAGCUGCUUUAGAAAAAUGAAAAUAAAGCCAACAAUAUUAACUCUGCAAAAAAUAAAAUAUUAAACAUGUCCUCGGGCUGGGAGCAGUGGCUCACACCUGUAAUCCCAGCAUUUUGAGAGGCCGAGGCGGGCAGAUCACUUGAGGUCAGGAGUUUGAGACCAGCCUGGCAAACACGGCGAAACCCCAUCUCUACUAAAAAUACAAAAAUUAGCUGGGUGUGGUGGUGCGUGCCUGUAAUCCCAGCUACUUGGGAGGCUGUGGCAGGAGAAUCGCUGGAACUGGAGAGGCAGUGGUUGCAGUGAGCCAAGAUGGCACCACUGCACUCCAGCCUGGGUGACAGAGCAACACUCUGUCCCAAAAAACAAAAAACAAAACAAACCCAUGUCCUUACUUGUAAGUCUCUUUCCCACACUUCCAGUCAGCAUGCGAUUGCAACAGCAUAGGUAAGAUGGAUUCUAGUCCCUAAAAUUCAAUACUCUCCUGAACCUUCUCCUACAGACGAGACUCUGCAAUUCAGAGGCCUCUUCUCAGUCUGUUCACUAGGUCAUUCAGAGUAUGCCACUAAUGUAGGAAGAAAGUAUUUUGAUUGACAGCAUCAUGAAUGUUUAAUCCUUUCAAGUAUGUUAUCUAUUUGGAAUGUAUGCAAUAAAUUCACUUUCAUGAACACUA